CCGGGCCGCGCGCUGAGGAGCCGCCCGGUCGCCUGCGCGCUCCCUCCGGCGGCGUCCCCAGCCCGCGGCCCCUCUGCUGCCGGCCCCCGGCUCGCCGGCUGCGGGAGUGGCCUCAAGAUGGAUGAAGACGGCGGCGGCGAGGGUGGUGGCGUGCCUGAAGACCUCUCAUUAGAAGAGAGAGAAGAACUUCUAGACAUUCGUCGAAGAAAAAAGGAACUUAUUGAUGACAUUGAGAGGCUGAAAUAUGAAAUUGCAGAGGUGAUGACAGAGAUCGACAAUCUAACUUCCGUAGAGGAGAGCAAAACGACUCAGAGGAACAAACAGAUAGCCAUGGGAAGAAAGAAAUUCAACAUGGAUCCCAAAAAGGGAAUUCAGUUUCUAAUAGAAAAUGACCUGCUACAGAGUUCCCCAGAAGACGUCGCCCAGUUCCUUUAUAAAGGAGAAGGCCUAAAUAAGACCGUCAUUGGGGACUACCUGGGUGAAAGGGAUGAAUUUAAUAUUAAAGUUCUUCAAGCCUUUGUUGAACUCCAUGAGUUUGCUGAUCUCAACCUUGUACAAGCCUUAAGGUAAGUAUGAUCAUUUGCUGGGUGUAGAGUGGAUGGGGAAGGCCAGAGGACCACUGCCUGGGCAGCAGUGGCGGUGAAUUGACUCCAGGUAACUUGGUGCCACACGAGUCUCACAGAUGCUGGCUCCUUUUCCGGAUGAUCCAGCUAAUGCUGUGUGACACUGAGCAGCCCUAGACAGGAAUUGGGGCACACGCUUAAGAUAAGGGCCGUGCUUUCCUCACUGUGGCCGCUGAUGCUCCUUCCAUUCCGUUUCCUUUUAUUUGUAAUGGUGUAUGGCAGUAGUCGAGUGCCUUGUUCCCAAGCUCUGUAUGGCGUGGCGUUGGUGCUCCAUGGGGUUACUUCCUUCCACACUUGACCCAAAGCACCAAACGCAUGGAUACCUGAGUGUGCCAGAGAGGAUGUAGGUGUCUCGCCAUUUUGGUGUCUGGGACACACUCCCUGGAUGCCCCCUUGAGCUGCCCUUCCUGCACGUUGUCUUCCUCCUGCUCUGCAAGCAGGAAGUUGUCUCGCUUCCUUCCUUGGUGCCCUGGCUGAGUCGCGUGGGCUCUUCAUCUGUUCUGGGCCUUGACCCUGAGCCAGCACUCAGCAGCAUCCGGGGGAGAGGAGGCAGGGCUUCUGGUGGGAGUCGCCUCAGCCGGCCCUUGGACUAAGAAAAUCAGGCCGCACCUCGUCAUCUUCUCAAAUCUUCGGCUUCAUACCUUGUUCUCGUUUACGUGGACUGUUUGCUCAUGGCCUUACCUCAACUGCAGACUGCAAUGUUGGCAGCGUUUUUGUGGGACCCUCGUGAUGUUGUGCUCACAGCGCAGCCUGGGGCUGAACAGUGCGCUGAGAGUUCGCAACAUAUAAGAAUCCUGCAGCCGCAGUUCAGGCUUAUCAGAUUGCGUUUCUGGAAGCUGUACAUCCAGAGAAGGGUGCAGGCCUGGCAGUUCUUAUGGAGCUUCAGGCUGCCCGGGGAGGCGCAGAAGAUUGAUCGCAUGAUGGAGGCUUUCGCUUCUCGCUACUGCCUGUGCAACCCCGGGGUCUUCCAGUCCACAGACACGUGCUACGUGCUGUCAUUCGCCAUCAUCAUGCUCAACACCAGCCUCCACAACCACAACGUGCGUGACAAGCCCACGGCAGAACGGUUCAUCGCCAUGAACCGCGGCAUCAACGAGGGCGGGGACCUCCCUGAGGAGCUGCUGAGGAAUUUGUAUGAGAGCAUUAAGAACGAGCCAUUUAAGAUCCCGGAGGACGACGGGAACGACCUGACCCACACCUUCUUCAACCCCGACCGCGAGGGCUGGCUCCUGAAGCUGGGAGGGCGUGUGAAGACCUGGAAGCGCCGGUGGUUCAUCCUGACCGAUAACUGCCUCUAUUACUUUGAAUACACAACAGAUAAGGAGCCCAGGGGAAUCAUCCCGUUGGAAAACCUCAGCAUCAGGGAGGUGGAGGACCCCCGGAAACCCAACUGUUUUGAGCUCUACAAUCCCAGCCACAAAGGGCAGGUCAUCAAGGCCUGUAAGACUGAGGCCGACGGCCGCGUGGUAGAGGGGAACCAUGUGGUGUACCGGAUCUCAGCCCCGAGCCCGGAGGAGAAGGAGGAGUGGAUGAAAUCCAUCAAAGCCAGUAUCAGCAGAGAUCCCUUCUAUGACAUGUUGGCAACGAGGAAACGAAGGAUUGCCAAUAAAAAAUAGCUUUCCUGGCUAAAAGACCCAGGUAAAAGACCCAACCCCAGCAGAAAGACACCGCGGGCGGCCCCUCCGCGGAAGGCGUGGCAGGGAGGCAGUCGCCCUGCGGUGCAAGCUGCUGCUCCAGAGCAUACCGUGGCCCAGGUGGUAUCCCCAAGGCCUCGUGCCGUGGCUGGGGUCCUGGGAGGUGGUCGCCCUGCAGUGCAAGCUGCUGCUCCAGAGCGUACCGUGGCCCAGACUGAUCCUCGAGGCCUCCUGCCGUGGCUGGGGUCAUGGUCGGCUGCGCAUGUCCAGAAGCAUUUCCUUCCUGCGACCAUCCCGGCGCCCCUAGGGGGAGAAGCCAGGACAGCAGCUUCCGCUGUCUCCACAGCAGACACGGGACGGAUUCCACAGACGGGAGCCUCAUUCGUACCAUGCCAAACGCAUUCACUCGGGGCAGUAUUAACCGUUCUAGAAAGCCACUGUUUUAUAGCAAAACAGGAAAGGAAAAGCUACCAGUUUUUUAUUCAGAAUUUUUCUCAGAUAUAUAGGAUUAUAGCUUUUAUAUGCCUUUUUAUAUUCUGAAAUUAUAACAAAAGAUACUUUCUAACAGUAGUAUUUUUAGAAUGGCAGCUAUAAAGUUAACUCCUGGACACAAGUAUAUACUGUGCACUGAAAAAAUAUCCAUCUACACAGCACCCAAGGGGAGGGCUGGGGGCACCGGCACGGGGGCAGCGUGCAGCCCUGCCCUGUCAGGCUGUCAGACAAGCCCCGGGGGGCAGCAGGUGGGCUCGGGACGGGCUGGGGGAGGGACGGCCAUGGCACUUGGGGGCUCCAGGGUGACUCCCAUGAGGCCUCCCUUCAACCAGGCUUUUUGGCCCCACAAAUACUUUAAGCAAAUCAUUAAAAUUAUAACAGUUAAUGGUUUGGGGGUGUUUAGGCUGUAACUGCUAACUCCUAGGAAACAGCCUUUUCCCUGGACACAGAUGGUCCAUACGCUGAGCCACGUGAAACUGCUGAUGUUUUGUUUAGAUGCACACACAUGGCAGCGUUUCAUACAGGUCAGCAGGUUAGACCGGCUUUUGACCAUAUUCAUCGCUAUUUAAAACCUGUGGCAAAAUGAACGCUUAUUUUACAGACUUUCUAAUUUGACCAGAUUUCUUAAUGAAUAGACACAGAAUUAACUAAAAACAGUCUCACCCCAUGUAGUGCGCCGUGUCCUGAGAGAGGUGCCCUCCCUACGAGGAGGGAAGAACAGGCCCUGGGGUGCAGAGGCCCGGCACGUAGAGAACCCAGAUAGACGCCGGUGGUGGAACUGGUCAAACUCCACGCCCGCCUGGGAGGUUGUCAGGUUGCUGUGGAUGUAAGGAUAGGAGGUGCCCAGUGCUCCGCUCAAGGAAGGCUGGAUCUGGGCCCCACCUACAGAGAGGGCUCAGGGCUGGACCGGGGGCAUUGUGUGCUUGGGCCGACCCGGGCCGGUGGCAGACGCUGUUCUCUGUCGGGAGAUUUGCGUCCCCAGGACCCUGUUACACAGUGGGCUGUUGGGUUGGUGGCUGGCUUUUCCUCUAUGGACUUCCUCUUCCUGCCCCACCUGCAUAGGCACACACACCUUGAAUCUGCACCCUCUGGAGGGCAUCUGUACUCCUGUGCAAAAUGCCCAGUCCAGAGACAAAACCUCAGACUUUGUGCACCUAGGUUUCCUUCUCAGCAGCGGAGACUGUUCUUUGAGUUGCCUUGAAGUGGAGGCCGAGCGGCUGCGGGCCCUUCGCCUCCCUGCGGCUGACCUUGAUGUAGCUUUAAGUCACACUAGACUGCAGAGGGGUCCGAGGCCAGAAACCCCUGUCCUGCAUCAGACUUUCAUUCCCACGUUCUUAGGCUUUGUUACUGAUACCUCAAAUCGGAAGUUUUAGUUCUGAGAAAGGCAAGUCAGCGUUCUUGAAAUGCCUGACUGGUAGAUAUGCAACUCUGGCCUCCAGUCUUCCAUGAAAAUAAAUGCUGCCUGGACCCCCACCCAGACCACACACUGACGGCCGGCUCCGGCGGUGCCCACCCCUCAGGCUGGCCCGGCACCCAAGACUGGCCACAGCCAGCUCUGUCAGCAUGUUGUGCUCGGACAAGCUGUUUCCUUCUUCUGACCAACCCAGGUGUGACCUGGGGAUGCAGAGCUUUCUGUUUUGGGUGUUGGGAGAAGCAGCAGGAAGGAGUCGCCAGAUGAUCAAGCUCCCCCUUUGCUGUCAUCUGUGAAUGAGCUUCGCCAGGUGGUGGGCACCUGGGAGCCAUGCAGAGGCUGUGGUGCUGAGUUAGACUCCAGGUACUUUGUGGUCAAAGGAAAUCGCCUAGCUCCAGGCUGUGUUAGGACAGUAUUAGCAUGAAGGCUGUGCGACCAUCAUGCCUGCUGAUCCUUGAGGCAGGCCUGGUCCAGAAAACUCUGGGUCAGUGACUGCGCAGGGCCAGCCGCUACCAGGACGGCCCUGAAACAGGACACAUCUGUUUUUUGUCCCUCACCCUGGGCAGGCCGCGUCACAAUCACAGUCCUCCUCCUCCCCACCCUGACGUCUGAGCGCAGGGCUUGAAUUGUUAGUCCCAACUCUGGCCAAAGAUACUUUUUUCCAGAGACAGAGGCCAGGAGGCAGUGAGGGGAGCCCCGCGGGGAGGCGGCGGCGACUGCCACAGCCCUUCCAGCCUGUCUUGCUGGCCGCCCUGGUUCAUAUUUGAGUUUAAUUGUACUGACCCUGGACCCAGAUAAGCAGCAACUUUGUGUCUUUGGGGUCACAGAACAUUUUGGGGCAGUUUAAUGUGGUACCAAACUGAAAAUAGGAGCUAUUUAUAGAUGGAGCAGCACUUAGUGCUUCAUAGAAAGCAAUGCCUAUUUUUAAAGUUACAAACGCAGAUAUCUACAUAGAUAUGCUUUGCUGAGAAGUUAGGUCUGUGGUAGACCAGAAACCACAAAUUGACUUUUUUUCUUAGAAAAUAUUUCUAUUUGCGGUAAAUAUAGUAAUAUGUAAAUAAUGUACAUCUGUUGAUUUCUGGAGUGUCUGUUAUUCAAUGAUGUAUAUACUCCCACAGCUCGCAUGAAGGAACAGCCUCUAUUGAUACUUGGUUGUAAAGUGAAGUAAGAUUGGAGGGUGGAUGGCUGUCAGAGCUCUUGCAGAUACUGUGUUCACUAAAUAAAAAUCACAUGUAUUGUUAAAA